AGAAGUUUUCUGACUCCUUUCGGAGGAGCCUCCGGGACCCCGGGGAGUAACAGGUGUCUGGAGGCUGAAGGGUGGAGGGGUUCCUGGAUUUGGGGUUUGCUUGUGAAACUCCCCUCCACCCUCCUCUCUCGCACCCACCCACCCCCUCACCCCCUUCUUUUUCCGUCCUUGGAAAAUGGUGUCCAAGCUCACGUCGCUCCAGCAAGAACUCCUGAGCGCCCUGCUGAGCUCCGGGGUCACCAAGGAGGUGCUGGUUCAGGCCUUGGAGGAGUUGCUGCCAUCCCCGAACUUCGGGGUGAAGCUGGAGACGCUGCCCCUGUCCCCUGGCAGCGGGGCCGAGCCCGACACCAAGCCGGUCUUCCAUACUCUCACCAACGGCCACGCCAAGGGCCGCUUGUCCGGCGACGAGGGCUCCGAGGACGGCGACGACUAUGACACACCUCCCAUCCUCAAGGAGCUGCAGGCGCUCAACACCGAGGAGGCGGCGGAGCAGCGGGCGGAGGUGGACCGGAUGCUCAGUGAGGACCCUUGGAGGGCUGCUAAAAUGAUCAAGGGUUACAUGCAGCAACACAACAUCCCCCAGAGGGAGGUGGUCGAUGUCACCGGCCUGAACCAGUCGCACCUCUCCCAGCAUCUCAACAAGGGCACCCCUAUGAAGACCCAGAAGCGUGCCGCUCUGUACACCUGGUACGUCAGAAAGCAACGAGAGAUCCUCCGACAAUUCAACCAGACAGUCCAGAGUUCUGGAAAUAUGACAGACAAAAGCAGUCAGGAUCAGCUGCUGUUUCUCUUUCCAGAGUUCAGUCAACAGAGCCAUGGGCCUGGGCAGUCCGAUGAUGCCUGCUCUGAGCCCACCAACAAGAAGAUGCGCCGCAACCGGUUCAAAUGGGGGCCCGCGUCCCAGCAAAUCUUGUACCAGGCCUACGAUCGGCAAAAGAACCCCAGCAAGGAAGAGAGAGAGGCCUUAGUGGAGGAAUGCAACAGGGCAGAAUGUUUGCAGCGAGGGGUGUCCCCCUCCAAAGCCCACGGCCUGGGCUCCAACUUGGUCACUGAGGUCCGUGUCUACAACUGGUUUGCAAACCGCAGGAAGGAGGAGGCAUUCCGGCAAAAGCUGGCCAUGGACGCCUAUAGCUCCAACCAGACUCACAGCCUGAACCCUCUGCUCUCCCACGGCUCCCCCCACCACCAGCCCAGCUCCUCUCCUCCAAACAAGCUGUCAGGAGUGCGCUACAGCCAGCAGGGAAACAAUGAGAUCACUUCCUCCUCAACAAUCAGUCACCAUGGCAACAGCGCCAUGGUGACCAGCCAGUCGGUUUUACAGCAAGUCUCCCCAGCCAGCCUGGACCCAGGCCACAAUCUCCUCUCACCUGAUGGUAAAAUGAUCUCAGUCUCAGGAGGAGGUUUGCCCCCAGUCAGCACCUUGACGAAUAUCCACAGCCUCUCCCACCAUAAUCCCCAGCAAUCUCAAAACCUCAUCAUGACACCCCUCUCUGGAGUCAUGGCAAUUGCACAAAGCCUCAACACCUCCCAAGCACAGAGUGUCCCUGUCAUCAACAGUGUGGCCGGCAGCCUGGCAGCCCUGCAGCCCGUCCAGUUCUCCCAGCAGCUGCACAGCCCUCACCAGCAGCCCCUCAUGCAGCAGAGCCCAGGCAGCCACAUGGCCCAGCAGCCCUUCAUGGCAGCUGUGACUCAGCUGCAGAACUCACACAUGUACGCACACAAGCAGGAACCCCCCCAGUAUUCCCACACCUCCCGGUUUCCAUCUGCAAUGGUGGUCACAGAUACCAGCAGCAUCAGUACACUCACCAACAUGUCUUCAAGUAAACAGUGUCCUCUACAAGCCUGGUGAUGCCCACACACCACUUACUUCGUGCGCAACAACAAGGACCCUGUUUUCCACACCAUCACCCUCUGGGCAGCUGUCAUGGAAAAGCCCAGUGACCUGACCAGCACCUGCGAGAGGUCCCUGCUUACCUGACGGACGUCCUGCUGGCACCUCAGACAAUCCACUCUCAGGAGGCGCAGCCCGAAGCCCAGUUUCCCUUCUAUGCAGUAUUGCCACAAUGCCUCUCCCACGAUGUCAAGGACUCCUGUCUGUCCUGGAGGUGGGAGACAAGGAACCUCCGAAGAGGAAGCAAGAAAGCCGUACUGUCUAUGUUGUGAUCCUUCAUCGAACAAACUGAUGCGAAAACUUGAAUCUGUUACUGAAAUGAGGAGAGAAGGACAUGUGCUAUUGAACUGAGCCAAACACACUGUAAAUAUCCACAGACUCCCUCCCCUGCCCCCAUCCCAAAUGAUCUUGAGAUUUCUUUUAAAGAAGUAAAUUUGUCCAAUGGCUGUAAACUAUAAACUACUGUAAUUAAGUGCAAUUUCCCCUCUGUGUCCUCUCCCCUCUGCCCUGUAUAUAAUACUAAAGUGUCUAUUAGUUUUCUUUGUAAAGGUCAGAGUCAAAAUUUCAAAAGUGAUCUGUCCCCUCUCCCCUCAUGGAGAAACAUCCUAAGUGGGAAGUGAAGCCCCUUGUCCUCUCCCGCGGGCCUGGACACUUAUGGGGACAGCAUACCUUGGACUGACUACCAGCUAACUCCAGUCUCCUGACAUUAAGACACACCUCUGGAUCCCUGGAGGGGCUGAAUGUAGUGUGUCAGAGUAACAUGCCAGCUUCCUGUGGGCCAGGAGCUCAGCCGUGCACUCCCUAAGAAACCCCAGGGCAGGGAAACUGGCUGUUUGAUAGCAGAAGAAAAAGUUGCAGUCUCAGAAAGCCUUCCAUUAAAACAAUUUAUUUUAUCACUA